AGUCUAGUGCCCUAGACAUGGCACUCAGAGGAGGGAGAGCUGGGAUCCGGUUCCGCGCGCAGUGCUGAGUCUCCCCUGAUUUGCGGUAGUGGAGCAGUCCACCCGGAGAACUCAGGAGUUUUCGCAGGGCGAGGGGGAGGGCUGGAGCCUGGAACCCCCAUAUUCCUUGCACCUCUUGGGCCCGGGACAGGCAGCCCUUAGUCACUGGGGUGUCCAUAGUGCCCACGAAGGGCCAGCGUCCCAGAGGGUUCCCAGGUCAGGUUGGUGACGUGUGGGGCUUCCCUAACUUCGUAGGCAAAAUCUGCCAGACCCUCCCGGGGGAGCGGAGCUCCGAAUACCAGGGCCGACUCCGCUCCUGAGGCCGCUGAGCCCUCCUGCACCUGUCCGGCCCGGGAAGUGCCAUGGGACAGCUGAUCGCCAAGUUAAUGAGCAUCUUCGGGAACCAGGGUAAGGGGCGCACAGGGCAUCCAAGCGAGCGCUUUGAUCUCGCCCUCUUCUGGGACUCCUCUGAUCUGUGGUCGGACGCACGGGGGGACCUCGGGCUCCGAGGGUCGUAUAUGGGCGCUCCUCGACUGCCCCGCGGCCUCCCCUGCCCCCGUCCCUGCCUGCUCCUCUUGGGUCCCGGCGCUUCGGUGCGCCCCAGGACGCAAAGCUGGGCGACCCUCCUUUCUCCCCGCUAAACGGAGCCAGCGGCGGGGAUGGGGGGCUGCUGCGAGUUUCCUGCGAUUGUGACUUCGCGUUAUGCUCUUUCUCUAAACACCGUCUCUUGGCAAGCCCCGAAGCGCCCCGGGCCUUUCAGACACUUUUCUGGAAUGUGAAGGGAGGUGGGGGCUCAGCUGUCUUUUCCACCGUCCCGGAGUGGGGCAGGUGUCGGAGCUGGGUGGGAAGCAGACGCGGUACGGUGGGCAGAGGUCCCCAGCCUGCGGGGAGCGCUAUCUCCUUCCUGGGAGGUCUGGUGGGGGCACACAGUCCCUUGGUCUUCGGGUUUGGCCCUGACGCUGCCCUUCCUCCGACGCUUCCAGAGCACACGGUCAUCAUCGUGGGACUGGACAAUGAAGGAAAGACCACCAUUCUCUACCGGUUGUAAGUGACUCUCGGGCGGGGAGGGUAGAGAGCUGGGCCUCCCACCAGACUGACAGGCAGGGGGACCAAUCACUGGAGCUCUUCCCUGGGUUCCCGGGCUCCUCUGUAGUCCGGAGGAGCGAUUGGGCACGCUGCUUGGACCUUCCUAGUACUGCGGCUCCUCGGUCUGGCAUUCAAAUCCUGCACCGUACAGGCAACCCUAGCUCCCACUGCUUUCCUCCAUCUUCCCGGGGGCCCUGCCAAACCCAGCUCCAGGCCUGCCAAGUGUCCCAAACUGCCUCCCUGCUCUUCGCUCCCUCUAGCGGCAGGUCCCUCCUUUCUCACCCCUGUCCCCUCUGCCAGUUAACUUUCUUCCCCUUCUUCAAACCCAAAGGCUCACUGAGGCUCUGUAGCUCCUGGUCUAGCAAGCCUGGCACAUAUGGGUGGUGCUGAGUAAAUACCGAUCGCAGCUUUCCCCGAUAUUCGCUCUCUGGAUGGCACCUCUCCCAUUUUACAGCCUCCAAAGUACUUUACUUAGGAGAAGCUUUUCCAUGAAAAAGUAAUACAUGUAAUGAUUUUAAAAAAUUAUAAAGGAAAAUUUCAAACAAUGGAGGAAUACACGGUGAAAAGUAAGUUUCCUUCUUGCCUCUGGCUCCUAGUUUUCCUCCUAUUGUAACUUUGCGUAACUUUUCAGAAGCAUUAUUUACAUAUAAAAGCAUGUGUAUAUUUUCUAUGUCACUUUAAACAAAGCACCUCUCUGAUGUCCCUCACUGUGUCUGUCUCAUUUUUCUAAACUCUUGCUCCUCAAAGUGUGGUCUACAGACCAGUCACACAGGCAUCACCUGAAAGCUUAUUAGGAAUGCAAAACCAUGGCCGGGCGCUGUUGCUCUCAAAGUGCCUGUAAUCGCAGCACUUUGGGAGGCCGAGGCGGGCGGAUCACCUGAGAUCAGGAGUUCAAGAGCAGCCUGGCCAACAUGGUGAAACCUCGUCUCUACUAAAAAUACAACAACAACAACAACAACAACAACAAAGGGCUGAGCAAGGUGGCUCACGCCUGUAAUCCCAGCACUUUGAGAGGCUGAAGUGGGUGGAUCUACCUGAGGACAGGAGUUCGAGACCAGCCUGGCCAACAUGGCGAAACCCCAUCUCUACUAAAAAAAUAUAAAAAUUAGCUGGGCGUGGUGGCACAUGCCUGUAAUCCCACCUACUCUGGAGGCUGAGGAAGGAGAAUCACUUGAACCCGGGAGGCAGAGGUUGCAGUGAGCUGAGACUGCGCCACUGUACUCCAGCCUGGGCGACAAAGGGAGGCGGAGGUUGCAGUGAGCUGAGAUUGUGCCACUGCACUCCAACCUGGGCGACAGAGAGAGACUACAUCUCAAGGAAAAAAAAAAAAAAAAAGCAAAACUGUGGCCGGAUGCGGUGGCUCAUGCCUGUAAUCCCAGCACUUUGGGAGUCCAAGGUGGAUGGAUCACUUGAGGUCAGGAGUUCGAGACUCGCCCAGCCAACAUGGCGAAACCCCGUUUCUACAAAAAUACAAAAAUAAGCCUGGCGUGGGGGUGUGCUCCUGUAAUCCCAGCUACUCAGGAGGCCGAGGCGGGAGAAUUGCUUGAACCUGGGAGACAUGAUCGUACCUACACUCCAGACUGGGCGACAGAGUGAGACUCUGUGAAAGAAAGAAAGAGAGAGAGAGAAGGAAAGAAAGAGAGAAAGAAAGAAAGAAAGAAAGAAAGAAAGAAAGAAAGAAAGAAAGAAAGGCAAAAGCCUGGACCCCUGCCCAGACUCACUGGGUCAGAAUCUGCAUUUUGACAAAACUCUCAGGUCAUUCAACUGCAUAUUAAAGUUUGAGGAGGCUGGGCUCUGUGGCUCAUGCCUGUAAUCCCAGCACUUUGGGAGGCCAAGGCAGGAGGAUCUCUUGACAGGAGCCCAAGGUCAGGAGUUCAAGCUUGACCAAUGAGGUGGUCCAUAUGUGUCCCACCAUUGGCAGCAACGUGGAGGAGAUCAUUCUGCCGAAGACCCACUUCUUCAUGUGGGACAUAGUGAGACCUGAGGCUCUGAGCUUUAUCUGGAACACAUACUACUCCAACACUGAGUUUAUCAUCCUUGUGAUUGACAGCACGGACCGGGAUCGGCUGCUGACCACUCGGGAGGAGCUAUAUAAAAUGCUGGCCCAUGAGGCUCUACAGGAUGCUUCAGUCCUGAUAUUUGCCAAUAAGCAGGACGUGAAGGACUCCAUGAGGAUGGUGGAGAUCUCCCAUUUCCUUACUCUCAGCACCAUCAAAGACCACUCGUGGCAUAUACAAGGCUGCUGUGCCCUCACCAGGGAAGGGUUAGUGGCUGCCCUACCUGGAUCUCUAGGGCCUGGCUGAACCAAUGGAUGACUGACCAUCAGAACCCUUCUCCUGCCUCUCUCCUGUGAGAAUCUGGUUCACAGUUGGCUCCUGGGCCAAGCCAAUUUGGCAUCUCCCCACAGGUGAGAUGUGGUGGGUAAGCCACAAGCAGACAGCAUCCCUGCUCUCAGGGGCUUGUUCUAGUGGAGAAAGAGGUAGCAC